ACACAAUUCCUUUAGUGUUUUCAAUCACCCAGUACUCGGUUCUCUUAGAGCAAAAAUCCUUUGGUGCUAGCUCAGUGUUAGGAAACGUCUUUAUCUCAAUGGCAGAGCGUUCUAUACCAAUUCAAAGGAGUUCAACAAUAAAAUUGAUUUGGCACUUGGUGCCUGCAGUAACUGGUGUACUGCCAUAUUUUUCCAAUUAAGAAAAUAUGUGGCAUGCGUGGAAUCACAUAUUUAAGCAAGCAAUUAAGUUGUUUAUGACACGGUCUGUUCCUGUUUAGAUCAGUAAUUGGAAAUUUGGGGACAAAAAUAGAGAUUUUAUUAAGUCUAUGGAUCAACUUGAAAUUUGGACAUCUCCUCGAAGCCCCAAAACUUUGAGUGGCAUCCACUGUGUAGAUGACAUGUAAUAGACAAAGCCUUCCCACCUCAUUGGCAGAAUUUGAAGGGUGUGUUUUCAUAUUUAAAUUUCAAUACAAUAUCAGUAAAAAUACUUUGCUAUUAAAUUGGCCCAUAAUGUUUACUAUAAUGUUCCUUCCUAAAGAAAGGACAAAUGUCCACAAAACUAACUCUGAGAACUAGAAAAUACGGCAAUAUUUAAGAUCACCGUAGCUAGAAUGCCCGGCAGGGCCGAGAUCUAGCGACUCUUCUUCCUCCAAACCAGCACCAGGUCUUCCUAAAUUUGUAAAGUGGUGGAGUUACCGUCAAGGUGCCCAGUGCAGCCUCCCGGCCAUGAGUCCACAACUACAGGCCCGAACUACAGGUUCGCCAGCGCGCCUGACGGCGAGGUUCAGGUCUGAACCCCCGGCGGGCGCAGUUCCUGGGAUUGUUGAUUUCCAAGCUCAGGGCAAGUAUUAAUUUCUCUGCAGACCGGCUCUUCCGGAAAUGAUUUUUAACACCCAUGCUGGCCUGGAUCCUGCGCUGGGAAGAACUGCAAACAGCCUCGACUAUCUAAACUCAGCUUUGACUUCUUAAAACCCGGAGUCUCUGAUUCGGGCGCAGAGGAUAAAGGUUCCAGGGGGAUAUAUAUAUGGUGGCUGUAUAUGCUCACACUAGAAGAGCUCCUGUUUUUAAAGGGAGGAGAAGGACAGGAAAGUGGCAACGGAUGUGUGCAAACCCAGAGCAGAAAAAUUCAUAUUUUAUUAAACAUCCGAGCUGCUGGUUGCAUGAAAAGGCUUUGAGCAACCAAUAGAAACCGAGGAUCGCGAAUAUUCCGCUUGAACCUGUUGAUCUCUGUGGGUUAAGCGUUUAGGGUCGAGUCUGCGUUUCCACGAGGGAGGGCGAAGAGAGAACAGAAAGAGCGGUUGCUUUCGCCCGCCACCGGAGGCUGGUUUUCCGCCUCCUGCCUUCUGGCCCGGCUUGGGCGGCGAGCCCUUUGGGCAGCCAACAUGGCGUGGGCGCCUGUGCUCGUGCGACCCCGGUCGGGCAGGCGGGACGGAGAUUACCUGGCUGUCCAGGGGACCUUAUGCAGGGUUUGGCCCGAGCCCAGGGGCAGCGAGGGGCGUCUGCGGAUGCGGCUCCCUGUGCGGCACAACACCGGGGUCUGUUGCUCUCGCUGAUACCUUUCGGCCCAAUUGUUCCUAAAUUAGACCAGCAAGUUUGCGGUAGGCAGAGAGCCAGCGGUGGUGAGAGCUGGCCUGAGAACGAGCCAGCCUUCUGGGAAUGGCCGGUGUGAGAGGCCAGUGGGUGGCCUUGCCGCGCCCUUAUGUCCAGACUUUGCUCUGUGAGAGGCCUGGCGCUGCGCCUUUGAUUUCUGUGAGUGCUGCGGAGCAAGUGAGUGCGAAAUGUCCCCGGAGCUGAAAGAUCGCAAAGAGGAUGCGAAAGGGAUGGAGGACGAAGGCCAGACCAAAAUCAAGCAGAGGCGAAGUCGGACCAAUUUCACCCUGGAACAACUCAAUGAGCUGGAGAGGCUUUUUGACGAGACCCACUAUCCCGACGCCUUCAUGCGAGAGGAACUGAGCCAGCGACUGGGCCUGUCGGAGGCCCGAGUGCAGGUUUGGUUUCAAAAUCGAAGAGCUAAAUGUAGAAAACAAGAAAAUCAACUCCAUAAAGGUGUUCUCAUAGGGGCCGCCAGCCAGUUUGAAGCUUGUAGAGUCGCACCUUAUGUCAACGUAGGUGCUUUAAGGAUGCCAUUUCAGCAGGUUCAGGCGCAGCUGCAGCUGGACAGCGCUGUGGCGCACGCGCACCACCACCUGCAUCCGCACCUGGCCGCGCACGCGCCCUACAUGAUGUUCCCAGCACCGCCCUUCGGACUGCCGCUCGCCACGCUGGCCGCGGAUUCGGCUUCCGCCGCCUCGGUAGUGGCGGCCGCAGCAGCCGCCAAGACCACCAGCAAGAACUCCAGCAUCGCCGAUCUCAGACUGAAAGCCAAAAAGCACGCCGCAGCCCUGGGUCUGUGACGCCAACGCCAGCACCAAUGUCGCGCCUGUCCCGCGGCACUCAGCCUGCACGCCCUCCGCGCCCCGCUGCUUCUCCGUUACCCCUUUGAGACCUCGGGAGCCGGCCCUCUUCCCGCCUCACUGACCAUCCCUCGUCCCCUAUCGCAUCUUGGACUCGGAAAGCCAGACUCCACGCAGGACCAGGGAUCUCACGAGGCACGCAGGCUCCGUGGCUCCUGCCCGUUUUCCUACUCGAGGGCCUAGAAUUGGGUUUUGUAGGAGCGGGUUUGGGGGAGUCUGGAGAGAGACUGGACAGGGGAGUGCUGGAACCGCGGAGUUUGGCUCACCGCAAAGCUGCAACGAUGGACUCUUGCAUAGAAAAAAAAAUCUUGUUAACAAUGAAAAAAUGAGCAAACAAAAAAAUCGAAAGACAAACGGGAGAGAAAAAGAGGAAGGGAACUUAUUUCUUAACUGCUAUUUGGCAGAAGCUGAAAUUGGAGAACCAAGGAGCAAAAACAAAUUUUAAAAUUAAAGUAUUUUAUACAUUUAAAAAUAUGGAAAAACAACCCAGACGAUUCUCGAGAGACUGGGGGGAGUUACCAACUUAAAUGUGUGUUUUUAAAAAUGCGCUAAGAAGGCAAAGCAGAAAGAAGAGGUAUACUUAUUUAAAAAACUAAGAUGAAAAAAGUGCGCAGCUGGGAAGUUCACAGGUUUUGAAACUGACCUUUUUCUGCGAAGUUCACGUUAACACGAGAAAUUUGAUGAGAGAGGCGGGCCUCCUUUUACGUUGAAUCAGAUGCUUUGAGUUUAAACCCACCAUGUAUGGAAGAGCAAGAAAAGAGAAAAUAUUAAAACGAGGAGAGAGAAAAAUAAUAUUAACACAAAAAAAUGCCACAGACAAUGAUUUCUCUGAGAAAUUAUUAUGGCAAAACUGUCUGGACUGCUGACAGUAAAUUCCGGUUUGCAUGUUACUUGUAUUCCAUUGAUGGUGUGUCUCCUCCCACCCCCUUAUCUCCCAUGCACUCACUCCAUUUUCAUCUUCACUAUGAAAAACAAUACCAAAAGUAUCUGGAAAUUGAUAUAUAUAUAUCCAUAUAUAUAUAUCAUAUAUUUGCCAUAUAUAUAUAUAUAUAUAUAUAUAUAUAUAUAUAUAUAUAUUUGCCCUGUCUUUGAUCCUGGGGAACAAAAGAAAAAAGUCAGAAAGGGAAAAAAUUACACUCAUUGUCCUAAGAAGACAGAGGUGGGCAGAAUAUGUGGGGAAAGGAAAAAGAAAACAAGACCACCAAAUGAAAUAAUGAAGGUACAGCGCCUCGCUGUGCCAGACACAGUAGGCGCUCAAUCAGUAUUAGUUCCCACCAUUCCCCUUUUCUUGUGUUCCUUCUUGUUGGUUUCCUGAAGUCCUAUUUGAAGACAGUGGUUUAUUUCCCCCUCUCUAUCCCGUCAAAUUCACCUUAAAUAACACCCAGCUAGAUACAGGCACUAGGUUUGUGUAAGAUAUGUUGAUACACACGAACAAAGUUUAUUUUGACUAUAAUGUGUGGACUGACUUUCAACAUUUGCAUUUUAUCUCACAAAGGUGUAUCUAUUCAAGUAACCUUUUUUUUUUGUUUGUUUGUUUCUUUUUUGUUUUUUUUUUUCUUUUGGUUGUUUGUUUCAAUUCAUGUAGCUAUUUAAACUGGGAUACCUUGGACUAAGCCAGUCUGUAUCCCAAUUCGCUAGCAAGCCUAAGUUUGUGGGGUUUUGUUUUUGUUUUUGUUUUACCUUCUAAUUUACAAGAAAGAGGAAAAGCUCUUCUAACUGAACUUUGGUAUGCGGUUGAGCUUUGUAACUAUUUGUUCUCCAUGAAAACAAAAUUAUUUAUAUUUGACAUAUUUUUUUCUAGUGUAUUAAGUUAUUUUAAACAAAAGAUGUUAUCUCAUGACGUGUUGUCAGUACAAAAUGUGUCGCCUCCAAUUCUGUUAAACCUUUUAAAUAAGUGCCAAGUUAUUAAUUGAAGACACUUUGCGAUCAAUUGAAUGAAAAUAUCGUUUCAUUUGAUGGGGUUCGAGUCAUCUUUGUUCCUGUUACUAUUAAAAUAUCCGGGAUAGUCUUUCCCUUUUGAUUAAUGCGUAUCACUCUCUCGAAUAUACCAACUUGGAAAAGC